GAAUGAGGUACUGAGGGCCAAGGUGUUGGAAGUUCCUAAUUCUUUCCUCGGUUAACUGUGAAACUCUGCGUAUUGGGAAGGCCUGGCCUCAGUCAUCAGGCCAGGAGAGGUACUGGACGCCGCGCACGCACUCGUCUGCCAGCGAGGCCCAAAGGGGAAGCCUAGCGGAGCUCAGUGUGGCAGCUGCUGGCCUCUGGGCCGGUAAGAAUUGAUGGUCCCCUCCCUUAUUCCCCAGGCCCAAAGCUUUGACCCAGUUAGUGCCUGCUAGUUUCGUGUGCCUGGCUUGUGCCUUUGGCGCGGAACGUUUGGGAGACUCGGCCUUGCGGUCUUCUGACCUCACCCACCACGUACCUAGCUUGGCACUGGGUCCUUCAUGCCUCUCACUCGCUUCCUCUGAGGCACCUGGGUACUCUCUUGUCUCUUACCCGCUUAAUCUGAGUCCAUGUCCAAGUUCAUCAUUCUGUGUCUGACCGUGUCCCAGCCACCGGAAGAGAAGAAACUCCGGGUGUGACAUUAAUCCCACUGGGGGCUCGGGAGAACUGCCUUCUAAAAUCAGAGACUGUAUCCAUUUGUCUGGAGAGAAAUGAAAAAAAUAAGGACAAUGUAGGGAGGUAUUUUAAAGCUACUUGUCAAUACCAUGCUUUCCUGUAAUAUUUGUGGUGAAACAGUAACCUCAGAACCAGACAUGAAAGCUCACCUAAUUGUUCACAUGGAAAGUGAAAUUAUAUGUCCAUUUUGCAAGUUGUCAGGUGUGAAUUAUGAUGAAAUGUGUUUUCAUAUCGAAACAGCUCAUUUUGAGCAGAAUACACUUGAAAGAAACUUUGAGAGGAUAAAUACAGUACAAUAUGGAACUUCAGAUAACAAGAAAGACAACACCCUACAGUGUGGAAUGGAAGUUAAUUCAAGUAUUCUUUCAGGUUGUGCAUCUAAUCAUCCAAAAAAUUCAGCUCAAAACCUGACUAAAGAUAGUACUUUAAAACAUGAAGGCUUCUAUUCAGAGAACUUAACUGAAUCUAGAAAAUUCCUGAAAAGUAGGGAAAAACAGUCCAGCCUGACCGAAAUAAAAGGAUCUGUUUAUGAAACAACAUACAGUCCUCCUGAAUGUCCAUUCUGUGGAAAAAUAGAGGAGCACAGUGAAGAUAUGGAAACUCAUGUGAAAACAAAGCAUGCCAAUCUUUUAGACAUUCCAUUGGAAGACUGUGAUCAACCACUCUAUGAUUGUCCUAUGUGUGGGCUCAUAUGUACAAAUUACCAUAUUCUUCAGGAACAUGUUGACUUGCAUUUGGAAGAAAACAGCUUUCAGCAAGGCAUGGAUAGAGUCCAGUGUUCUGGUGAUCUACAAUUGGCUCACCAGCUUCAGCAAGAAGAAGACAGAAAGAGGAGAUCUGAAGAAUCAAGACAAGAAAUAGAAGAAUUUCAGAAGCUGCAGAGACAAUAUGGUUUAGAUAAUUCUGGAGGAUACAAACAACAACAACUACGAAAUAUGGAGAUAGAAGUAAAUAGGGGAAGAAUGCCUCCAUCUGAAUUUCAUAGGAGAAAAGCUGAUAUGAUGGAAUCAUUAGCUCUUGGUUUUGACGAUGGAAAAACAAAAACUUCCGGAAUUAUUGAAGCACUUCAUAGGUAUUAUCAGAAUGCUGCCACAGAUGUGAGACGGGUGUGGCUUUCUUCAGUGGUGGAUCACUUUCAUUCAUCUUUAGGCGACAAAGGUUGGGGUUGUGGUUACAGAAAUUUCCAAAUGCUACUUUCAUCAUUAUUACAAAAUGAUGCUUACAACGAUUGCUUAAAAGGUAUGUUGAUUCCUUGCAUUCCAAAAAUUCAAUCUAUGAUUGAAGAUGCAUGGAAGGAAGGUUUUGAUCCUCAGGGGGCCUCUCAACUUAAUAACAGGUUACAGGGAACAAAGGCCUGGAUUGGAGCAUGUGAAGUAUAUAUACUCCUGACCUCCCUAAGGGUAAAGUGUCAUAUUGUUGAUUUUCACAAAUCAACUGGUCCUUUGGGUACACACCCUCGCUUAUUUGAAUGGAUAUUGAACUAUUAUUCUUCAGAGGGAGAAGGGAGUCCAAAGGUAGUGUGUACAUCUAAACCUCCUAUCUAUCUUCAGCAUCAAGGUCACAGUCGAACUGUUAUUGGAAUUGAAGAGAAAAAAAACCGAACAUUAUGCUUACUAAUACUUGAUCCUGGAUGUCCUUCUCGAGAAAUGCAGAAAUUAUUAAAGCAAGACAUAGAGGCUAGCAGUCUCAAGCAACUUCGGAAAUCUAUGGGAAAUUUAAAACAUAAGCAAUACCAGAUAUUGGCAGUAGAGGGUGCUCUUUCUCUAGAGGAGAAACUUGCCAGGAGACAAGCUUCUCAAGUCUUUACAGCCGAGAAGAUUCCUUGAAGAAUCAAGCAUUUAAGCAUUUCAGUGAUUGAGAACAAUACUUUGUUUUCUAAAUGUAGAUAUUGAACUCCUUAAUACAAUUAUGAAUCUGUGAAUUCUCUUAAGUCUUAACAUAUAAUUUAAUUUCUAAAAUGCCUGUGUUAAUUGAAUUAUACCUAUCAUACUUCAUUGUUUGGUAAAUUAUUUCAAUAAAAUGUCUUGUUUUUGCAUUGUG